ACUUGGUCGGGAGGCGCCGGCCCAGCGAGGCCGCUGGGACUGUGCACUGAGGGGCGCUGACCGUUGGACGCGCGCUCCCCGCAGACCCUCGCUGAAGGAGCAGGGGGCGGCGCGCGUGCGCGGGGCGCCGGGCGGCGCGCGAGGGGGCGGAGCGGGGAGGCGUGCUGCGACCCCGGCCGGCUACAGCCUGCGGCGCGCGCAGAGCGCUAGUGGGGCGCGCGGCGCGCGCGCGGGGCGGGGGCGCGCGGAGGGGGGGGCUGCCCCGGGGCGGCCCCCCCAGGUCGGGGCGCGGCGGGCGGCGGCGGCGGGCGCGCGUCCCGUCCAGGUCCGGAGUAACCGCCGCCGCCGCCGCCAAAGCUCGCCAACAUGGCGGACCUGGAGGCUGUGCUGGCCGAUGUCAGUUACCUGAUGGCCAUGGAGAAGAGCAAGGCGACCCCGGCCGCCCGCGCCAGCAAGAGGAUCGUCCUGCCGGAGCCCAGUAUCCGGAGUGUGAUGCAGAAGUACCUUGCAGAGAGAAAUGAAAUAACCUUUGACAAGAUUUUCAAUCAGAAAAUUGGUUUCUUGCUAUUUAAAGAUUUUUGUUUGAAUGAAAUUAAUGAAGCUGUACCUCAGGUGAAGUUUUAUGAAGAGAUAAAGGAAUAUGAAAAACUUGAUAAUGAGGAAGACCGCCUUUGCAGAAGUCGACAAAUUUAUGAUGCCUACAUCAUGAAGGAACUUCUUUCCUGUUCACAUCCUUUCUCAAAGCAAGCUGUAGAACACGUACAAAGUCAUUUAUCCAAGAAACAAGUGACAUCAACUCUUUUUCAGCCAUACAUAGAAGAAAUUUGUGAAAGCCUUCGAGGUGACAUUUUUCAAAAAUUUAUGGAAAGUGACAAGUUCACUAGAUUUUGUCAGUGGAAAAACGUUGAAUUAAAUAUCCAUUUGACCAUGAAUGAGUUCAGUGUGCAUAGGAUUAUUGGACGAGGAGGAUUCGGGGAAGUUUAUGGUUGCAGGAAAGCAGACACUGGAAAAAUGUAUGCAAUGAAAUGCUUAGAUAAGAAGAGGAUCAAAAUGAAACAAGGAGAAACAUUAGCCUUAAAUGAAAGAAUCAUGUUGUCUCUUGUCAGCACAGGAGACUGUCCUUUCAUUGUAUGUAUGACCUAUGCCUUCCAUACCCCAGAUAAACUCUGCUUCAUCCUGGAUCUGAUGAACGGGGGCGAUUUGCACUACCACCUUUCACAACACGGUGUGUUCUCUGAGAAGGAGAUGCGGUUUUAUGCCACUGAAAUCAUUCUGGGUCUGGAACACAUGCACAAUCGGUUUGUUGUCUACAGAGAUUUGAAGCCAGCAAAUAUUCUCUUGGAUGAACAUGGACACGCAAGAAUAUCAGAUCUUGGUCUUGCCUGCGAUUUUUCCAAAAAGAAGCCUCAUGCGAGUGUUGGCACCCAUGGGUACAUGGCUCCCGAGGUGCUGCAGAAGGGGACGGCCUAUGACAGCAGUGCCGACUGGUUCUCCCUGGGCUGCAUGCUUUUCAAACUUCUGAGAGGUCACAGCCCUUUCAGACAACAUAAAACCAAAGACAAGCAUGAAAUUGACCGAAUGACACUCACCGUGAAUGUGGAACUUCCAGACACCUUCUCUCCUGAACUGAAGUCCCUUUUGGAGGGCUUGCUUCAGCGAGACGUUAGCAAGCGGCUGGGCUGUCACGGAGGCGGCUCACAGGAAGUAAAAGAGCACAGCUUUUUCAAAGGUGUUGACUGGCAGCAUGUCUACUUACAAAAGUACCCACCACCCUUGAUUCCUCCCCGGGGAGAAGUCAAUGCUGCUGAUGCCUUUGAUAUUGGCUCAUUUGAUGAAGAGGAUACCAAAGGGAUUAAGCUACUUGAUUGCGACCAAGAACUCUACAAGAACUUCCCUUUGGUCAUCUCUGAACGCUGGCAGCAAGAAGUAACGGAAACAGUUUAUGAAGCAGUAAAUGCAGACACAGAUAAAAUCGAGGCCAGGAAGAGAGCUAAAAAUAAGCAACUUGGCCACGAAGAAGAUUACGCUCUGGGGAAGGACUGUAUUAUGCACGGGUACAUGCUGAAACUGGGAAACCCAUUUCUGACUCAGUGGCAGCGUCGCUAUUUUUACCUCUUUCCAAAUAGACUUGAAUGGAGAGGAGAGGGAGAGUCCCGGCAAAAUUUACUGACAAUGGAACAGAUUCUCUCUGUGGAAGAAACUCAAAUUAAAGACAAAAAAUGCAUUUUGUUCAGAAUAAAAGGAGGGAAACAAUUUGUCUUGCAAUGUGAGAGUGAUCCAGAGUUUGUGCAGUGGAAGAAAGAGUUGAACGAAACCUUCAAGGAGGCCCAGCGGCUAUUGCGUCGUGCCCCGAAGUUCCUCAACAAACCUCGGUCAGGUACUGUGGAGCUCCCAAAGCCAUCCCUCUGUCACAGAAACAGCAACGGCCUCUAGCACCCAGAAACAGGGAGGGUCCUCGAGGAGGACACACCAGGGUCUCAGCCUUUUGGGGUGAACGAGGAUGAGGCAUCUGAUCUAUUCGCUACCGGGACUCCUCCAGGCUCCCGAGAGGAGUCGGGACCCUUCGGCUUGGGGUCAGCUCAGCUCCCUGCCUUGUCACAUUUGUCUGCAUUAGAAACUACUGAAGAAAUAAAAGUUCUUUUUCUUUGCUACACACUUUGGUACCUAUGAACCUAGAACUUGAAGUGACUCCUACUUAUCACGUAAAUUUUUAUGUCUGAUAUCAAACACAUCUUAGACUCCCCAGAAUGGAAUUUAAAGAUGUUCAGUGUUGGGUAACAGAUUGCCCUAAGCAUUGCCACAUAUUCUGUCUAGUCACUGCUGAUUUUCUAUGUCUUUGCUCCAUACUGCUGGGGGAUGGGAGAGCCACAGUGUGUUUCUUUUGUGCACUUCGCAACUGACUUCUUGUCCUGGGGUUAAAAGUUGAAGAUAUUUUCUGAUGAUAUUAAAAGUUGAAGAUAUUUCUGCACUUGGGCCCUCCUCUGGGAGCCGCACCCACAUGACUGCCCUGCCUCUGACCAGUCUGUUCCGGGGCCCCCUCAGCCAGGUGGGAAUGACGGACACGUACUAUCCAAGUGUAUGGGAUUAACUAAUCAUUGAAGGCAUUCAUCCGUCCAUCAUUGGAAAGAUUUACAGUGAUUCUGAAGGACAGGCCGUGGAGUUUUAGGUUUCAGGGGCAAGAGCAGUUUUCAAAAGUCUUUGAGUCCAGUGUGCACGAGUCGACAAGCAGUACCUGGCAUGCAGGAGCACUCAUGGGUGAGUCCGUCUCAGGUCUCGACAAUUAGCAGUUGUGUGACAGUCAUUCUGGUUCCUUCUGCCUGACCCUGGGAGACAUAUCAGUAAUGGAUGUACAAAAGCAGGUCUGUUUUAUGUCUUAGUAUAAUUUCAGAUGAAUUGUAUUGAAAAAAUGCUGAGGAAUGAAUGUGUCAAAAUGGGUUAACUGUGUAUAUUGACUUUCAUGUCGUCAUGCAUCUGUCAUGAAUGAAUGAUACUUUGCACUGGGCUGUACGACAGUGAGGACCUUAGGGCAUGAAGCCUUUUUCCUGGUCCCAGCAGCAUCUGCCCUGUGAAGUUUGUUUUCUCCCACUGCCUCCAGGCCCCACUGAUACCCCCAAAUAGAUGCUGGGUUAUGAGAACCAGCGAAAUCCCCCAUGUCAUCAGUCUUAAAAAAAAAAUUUUACAAAUCCACGUAUUUGUCCCAUUCUUGGAGUAGUUUUAGUGUAUGUCUUUACAUUAACUACUAACAGUAUAAAUAACUUGACAUCGUAAUUGUCUGCAUCCUGUCCUUGAUAUUUUUAGCAGUUCCAAAUCUUUGUUUUUGUAUUUGUUUGCUGUGUUCAUGGGCAAAGUAAGUACUUUUUAAUGCAGUUAUUUUGAGAGUUUGGAAGAUAAUUACCAAAAGGGUCCAUUAUUUCAUAAGAGUUACUUUGCAAAAAAAAAAAUGUGGGUUUUUUUUUUUGUCUAUCUCAACUACUAGUUGGGGUUUAAAUUAACAUACAUUUUCUACUAUCUGUUAUUUCCAGUGUGGGAGGAGGGAUGUACUACUUACAUGCAUUCUCCUUAUUUAAAAAGGAAGAAUAGUAUUCAAAUUCUGUUGAAACACACACACACACACACACACACACACACACACACUCCAGAAGCAGAAAAGCCAUUGUUCUUAAAGAGUGAAUGUCUUCCCAGCCCUGGUUAAUUAUAGCUGUGACUGAUGCCGUUCCCGUCUGCAUCUCAAGCUCAUAGGUUCUCAGCAUGUGCAGUUGAGGAUGCGCUGGGCCUCAUGCCUGUUCUAGAUCUCCAGGAUAAAGGGCCUGCUGUUGACUCCACCAGGGUCUGGGCUUAGCGUCUAAUAUCUCGUACCUAGGGCGUGAGCUGCACAAACGUGUUCAGAAAGAUUAUUCAACUUUCCCAUACUUGUUCUAAAAUUGAGCUGAUCCGCAUCUCUUUCAAAAACUAGAAUUUCUGCUCUAAGAAUAGAACAUAAGGCUCCACUCCCUUUUAGAAAAGAUAUAUGAAUUGGAAAAUGCUCUGAAAGUCCUUUUGCUUCAAACAAAAGUGUAAACUUUUACACUUCCCCAACUCACAUUUGAUUUGUAAUGAUAUGGUUGAGAAGUACAUCUAGAUGUCAUUUAUUAAAAGUGCUUUGUAAGACUAGAUUGAGCUGUUUCUGAGGGCGGUCACCAGUUGUGUUGGGGUCUGGUUUGAGUGCCUUCUGCCAAAAUGUUGUGAUGGAGGUGUUUCUGCGACCAGACACAGGAUACCGCUGUGUCUGCACCCGGUUGCCUGCAUGGCCAGAGGAAAAGUCAGUUGGAUUAAACAUCAUGGUAUACUUGGCUGUUGUUUUUUUUUAAUUUUUUAAUUUUUUGGGAUAGGGCCUCGCUCUGUCACCCAGGCUGGAGAACAGUGGGAUGAUCAUGGCUCACUGCAGCCUUGAAUUCCUAGGUUCAAGCAAUCCUCCCACGUCAGCCUCCUGAGUAGCUAGGACUACAGGUGCAUGCCACCUUUCCUGGCUAAUUUAUUUUUUGGGUAGAGAUGGGGUCUUGAACUCUUAGGCUCAAGUGAUCCUCCUUCCUUGGCCUCCCAAAAUGCUGGAAUUAGAGAUGUAAGCCACCAUGCCCAGCCAUAGUACUUGGAUGUUUUAGAAGGUUUUCCAAGUAUUACAUAAUUCCUAGAUGUUCACCCUUAUUACACUCCAACUAUUAAAAAGGUCAAAAUUCAGCCUAUUUUUUUUCAUUAUUUUAGAUUCCUGUGGUUGGGAUAUUUUAACAUUGAUGAGAAAAAUAAUUGAGGUUGAUAUUUUUACAAAAUCAUGCGGUAAUAAGUCUUGAUUUCAUGAUUCAAAAGAAUCAAUAAAGCCUAAAAAUAAUAGAUUACUUUAAGCUGCUAUGUAAGAUAUAUAUGGAAUAAAUUAAAAACCUUUGUGAAUUCAGGUUUAUUAUUUUUAACCUAAAACAUUCUCUUUGGUUCAUUCAUCCCCUCAUGUCAUGGGGGCUCAUUGGUUUUCCUUCUUUGUCAUAUUUAAGUAUGAUUUUUCAACAAAACUUCUAGAAGUCAGCUUAUUAUGUCACCAUUCAUGCAAAGUGCUCAUGCCUCUGAUUGGUCCAUUCACUGACGUGACAAUUUCAGGUCCUAUGUUUAAAAAGAAGGGGCUGGCCGGGCACGAUGGCUCACGCCUAUAAUCCCAGCACUUUGGGAGGCCGAGAGGGGCGGUUCACGAGGUCAGGAGAUUGAGACCAUCCUGGUUAGCAGAGUGAAACCCCGUCUCUACUAAAAAUACAAAUAAAAAUUAGCCGGGCGUGGUGGCGGGCGCCUGUAGUCCCAGCUACUUGGGAGGCUGAGGCAGGAGAAUGGCAUGAACCCGGGAGGCAGAGCUUGCAGUGAGCCGAGAUUGCGCCACUGCACUCCAGCCUGGGCGACAGAGCGAGACUCUGUCUCAAAAAAAAAAAGGAGGGGGGCUAAAUAUCCAGUGAGAUGCACUGAGGAAAGGAAGCAUUUUGCUGAAGACAGCAGCAGCAACAAACAAUGGUCUGUUUGUUGCAAACAAGAUGUAGCUUGAUUUCUGGUCUGACAUAUGCCAUAUACAGAUAUUAGAAACGACUGUUUGAAGGCCACACUGGUCAUCUACAAAGUAAUGUUUACCAAUUGACGACAGGGAUUUAACUAGAUUAAAAAGAUCAAAGUGUGGUUUUUCUCUGCUUUUUAAAAUUUCACUCGGAAUUUGUAGCUGGGCCAAUUCAACACAUUUUACUUUUCAGUGGAAUUGAUUUUUCUAAUGUUUCAGAAUUUUAACAUAUCAAGAAGAAAACAACGUUCUCAAAGUCUGGCCUCUUUAGCAUGAUGUAAACCUAUAGAAAUGCUUUGAAAUGUGCUGGUGUAAGAUAAGAGUUAUCUUGUAUGAUUUAAUCAUAUGCAGUGUUGUCUCAGUUACGUUCAGGGAAAUGUUUCUGUGUCAUUCAGAGAUGCUUGAUGAAUUAACACCUCCCACCCUGAGUGAGGGGUUGACUUGUUGGGAGAUGAUUUGGGCUUCACUGGGAUCUGUGACAGGUGGGGGCUGGGCUGGGUGUCACAAAGAGAAUAGUGGUAGAAAUCGGGCGAAGGAAGAAAGAAGUUACUGGUAAAAAUCAUUACACCAUAAAGCACCAAGGAAAUAACUGAGUUAAAAUAGGUGAAGUUUCUUUUUUCCCCCCUGUAACAGGAGAGUUUUCCUUAUGAUAAUUAUUCUGAGACUUGGUCACUUUGUUUUUGAAUGUGGAGCUGCUGAACUCAUUCAGAAGCCAUUUGCUGCCUAUCAGGACUUUCUGAAGAAGUUCUUUUGCCUCUGCCUACCCUCUGGCACCCUCCCAUGGAGGCACAGGGGACCCAGAGCUAAAGCAUUACCAGGCCAUCUCCAAAACACCCCGUGUGUGUGUGUGUGUGUGUGUGUGUGUGUGUGUGUGUGUGUGUGCACUUUGCAGCCCCCGAGGUGGAGAGGCAGUGUCUGGAUCACUGUGAAUGCAUUGCCCCAUUGGUCAGUUGGGGACACUGUUACAAAUCCACUGAAGUCCUGGUAAAACUGUCAAGAGUAACAGGCCUCUUCUGUUCUACCCUGCUCACUUCCACGGUGAGUUACCAGCCUGGGCAACACAGCAAGACCCCAUCUCUACAAAAAAAAUUUUUUUAAGUAAUUAACCGUUUAAAUUUUUUCCUAAAGAUUUAACAUGAUUUUUCCCUCCUAUGUAAAGUUUACUGGAGAGACUUGAAUUACUUAAAUUCAUGUUAAUAUGAUUUUUUUUUAAUCCAGGUCACAUUUUAACAAAGUUUAUUAUGAAACAAAUGAAAUUUGAACUCUAAAAUGGUACUCCUUGGCUUCCUCAAGUCACAAUGAACUUUAUAUUUUCUUUGUCCUUAAGGACUAAGAUAGUUGUUUUAUUUCAGCCGAAUCACAGAGAUAACCACUCCUGCAGGCCCCCACAGCUGGCCCAAAGGGGCUGUCUUUCUGACCUGGCUGUGUUAGCACUGAUUGAGAAACGCAGGCUCCCAAAUUUUAAAUUGCCUUUAUUAAAAACACAAACUACAGAAAAUGGGUUAAGAGUAUACGCAUUUCAUCAAACACAUAUAGGGGAAAAAAUCCUUCAAUUUAGAGUUAAAUAACUCAGCUUUGUAUAGUAGAGUUAGCGCUCCAGUAUCUAACAAUCUCAGAAUCAUCUCUGAAAACUGGUAACUAUGCUUCCAUUUUUAAUUUUGUCCUAAAUAUCAGAUGUCUUUGAUGUAAGGGUAGGGAAUGGAGAAAUAUUUUCAAUUGUGUAUUUGUAUUACAAAGAACUUGAAAUUUACUUUCUUAGUUGAUUAUAUUAAAUGAUGUAUAUAUUAUAUGUGGUUUAUAAGCUCAACACUGGCCAUUUUUUUAGUUUUAUUGUUAAAUGGUAUUUUUCUAUGUUUAAUUAUAAUAGAUCUGGCUUUUUCUGGAUAGCAUAAAGAUCACUGAACUAUAUAUAUAUAAGAAACAAGAGUUCUAUUUUAGCACAAAGGCAUUUUAUAUUAUUUAUUGAAUCCAUAAGUUUGUUUUCGUCAAAAACAUUCCAUAUUAUUUCUGCUCCUUUUUAUUUGUAUAGUUUGUUAUUUAAAGAAAUGGCAGUCCUUCCUGUUCUUAAUACAAUAAAAUUGAAAUAAUGCACCUAGUAAUGUGGCCGACAUCUCUUCUCACCACCAUGGACUGUUUUCAACAACAGUUGAUCUUCUGGUCUGUGCUGAGAGGCGCAUGCAUGUCUUUCGUCACGUCGGGCAGCACACCUGCUGUGAAAUACUGCUUUCAUCUACCUCUUCAGAAGGCUUCUUGCUUGUUGACAAGUACCGCAAAGGCUUUAUUCUGGACUGGCUAUCUCAUAAAAGGAUUUCUGUAAGACUUUGCAGUGUCAUUCCCUCAGAACCUAGGUUUGUUUCUAAAGCCACGGUAUUGUCCAGGAGCCCCUGUGUGUGGGGCAGGUAGCUAUCCCUCCCAUGUCAUUAGUAAUCCUUUAGGAUUUAAGGUACAACUGGACAGCAUCAUUCCUUCCCCUUAUUGUGCCAAAUCCCCACCAUCAGCCUUGCCAUUGCCUUAAGAUUUGAUUAUUGCACCCAAUUACCUAACCACUAAACAGAAAGGCCACCUUCACUCUUUGAAAAAGGCAAGCUGUGCUUAGAAACACUGCUUUUAAGAGUAGCACAUUUGAGUGUGACUUUUUCCCCCCUUCACUAUUUCAAAAUGGUUUUGAAAUGGGGUCUUAAAGGUAAGCGCCCUCAUACAUGACUGAAACUUUGUGAGAGGUCUUAUAUUUGAAUGGACCCUUAAUGAUUUAUGUGAAAUAGAAUGAAGUCCUGUCUCUGUGAGAGAACGUGCCUCCUCACUCAUUUGUCUCUGUCUGUUUUCAUAGCCAUCAAUAUAGUAACAUAUUUACUAUAUUCUUGAAUACCCUUGAAGAAAGAAAUCCGUUUUCUAUUGUGCAUUGCUAUACGAAGUGAAGCCAGUAAACUAGAUACUGUAAAUCUAGAUAUUGUACCUAGACAAAAUAUCAUUGGUUCUAUCUCUUUUUGUAUCUGUUGUGCCAGGGAAGGUUUAUAAUCCCUUCUCAGUAUACACUCACUAGUGCACGUCUGAAAUAGUAUCCCACGGGAGAUGCUGCUCCACGUCUGAGGUCACCUGCCCUGUGUGGGGCACACCACCGUCAGCACCACCGUUUUUACAGUUACUUUGGAGCUGCUAGACUGGUUUUCUGUGUUGGUAAAUUGCCUAUAUAAAUCUGAAUAAAAAGGAUCUGUACAAAGA